GUCUCUGGUAUCUCCCGCUGAGCUGCUCUGUUCCCGGCUUAGAGGACCAGGAGAAGAGGGAGCUGGAGGCUGGAGCCUGUAACACCGUGGCUCGUCUCGCUCUGGAUGGUGGUGGCAACAGAGAUGGCAGUGCGGCUGGAGUGUUAGGAGGGUGGCCUGAGCAGUAGGAUUGGGGCUGGAGCAGUAAGAUGGCAGCCGGAGCGGUUUUUCUGGCAUUGUCUGCCCAGCUGCUCCAAGCCAGACUGAUGAAGGAGGAGUCCCCUGUGGUGAGCUGGAGGUUGGAGCCUGAAGACGGCACAGCUCUGUGCUUCAUCUUCUGAGGUUGUGGCAGCCACGGUGAUGGAGACGGCAGCUCAACAGGAGCAAUAGGAGGGUACCCGUGGAGGCCAAGUGCGAUGUGCAUUUUGUAAGCACUUUGGAGCCACUAUCAAAUGCUGUGAAGAGAAAUGUACCCAGAUGUAUCAUUAUCCUUGUGCUGCAGGAGCCGACACCUUUCAGGAUUUCAGUCACAUCUUCCUGCUUUGUCCAGAACACAUUGACCAAGCUCCUGAAAGAUCGAAGGAAGAUGCAAACUGUGCAGUGUGCGACAGCCCGGGAGACCUCUUAGAUCAGUUCUUUUGUACUACUUGUGGUCAGCACUAUCAUGGAAUGUGCCUGGAUAUAGCGGUUACUCCAUUAAAACGUGCAGGUUGGCAAUGUCCUGAGUGCAAAGUGUGCCAGAACUGCAAACAAUCGGGAGAAGAUAGCAAGAUGCUAGUGUGUGAUACGUGUGACAAAGGGUAUCAUACUUUUUGUCUUCAACGAAUUAUGAAAUCUGUACCAACCAACGGCUGGAAAUGCAAAUGAAUACCGAAUUGGAAAAACAGAUUUCUAAUGAGGCUGAUAGUGAAGAAAUGAAAAUGUCUUCUGAAGUGAAGCAUAUUUGUGGCGAAGAUCAAAUUGAAGAUAAAAUGGAAGUGACAGAAAACAUUGAAGUCGUUACACACCAGAUCACUGUGCAGCAAGAGCAACUGCAGUUGUUAGAGGAACCUAAAACAGUGGUAUCCAAAGAAGAAUCAAGGCCUCCAAAAUUUGUCAUUGAAUCUGUCACUCUUCCACUAGAAACCUUAGUGUCCCCACAGGAGGAAAGCUCUUCAUUAUGUCCUGAGGAACAGUUGGUUAUAGAAAGGCUACAAGGAGAAAAGGAACAGAAAGAAGAUUCUGAACUUUCUACUGGAUUGAUGGACUCUGAAAUGACUCCUACAAUUGAGGGUUGUGUGAAAGAUGUUUCAUACCAAGGAGGCAAAUCUAUAAAGUUAUCAUUUGAGACAGAGUCGUCAUUUUCAUUAUCAGCAGACAUAAGCAAGGCAGAUGUGUCUUCCUCCCCAACACCUUCUUCAGACUUGCCUUCGCAUGACAUGCUGCAUAAUUACCCUUCAGCUCUUAGUUCCUCUGCUGGAAACAUCAUGCCAACAACUUAACAUCUCAGUCACUCCAAAAAUUGGCAUGGGUAAACCAGCUAUUACUAAGAGAAAAUUUUCUCCUGGUAGACCUCGGUCCAAACAGGGCCGUGGGUCUGGAUUUCCAAGAAAGCGGAGACCUCGAGGUGCAGGACUGUCGGGGUGAGGUGGCCGAGGCAGGUCAAAGCUGAAAAGUGGAAUUGGAGCUGUUGUAUUGCCUGGGGUGUCUACUGCAGAUAUUUCAUCAAAUAAGGAUGAUGAAGAAAACUCUAUGCACACUACGGUUGUGUUGUUUUCUAGCAGUGACAAAUUCACUUUGAAUCAGGAUAUGUGUGUAGUUUGUGGCAGUUUUGGCCAAGGAGCAGAAGGAGGAUUACUUGCCUGUUCUCAGUGUGGUCAGU